GCAGAACUCUGAUGUUUUAUAGCUAAAUCUUACGUGUAUUAUUUUAGAUAUCACAGCAUUGGCCUUAAAGCACGUGGUCAUGUCACCACUACUCUUGCCCCACUCACACACAUGCCUGAAGAACUGUGUGGAGACAGUGGGACAAGAAGAGGGAUAAGGACAGCCAGUGAUAGGAGUCCCCAGAUGUUAGUAGGAAGCAUGAAAGGCACUAGGACAUGUGCUGACUUAUGGAUACUCAACGUGGCUACGUUGGCAAAUGAGGCUUCAGAGAGUGACAGAAGUAUUUUGUGGGUGAGAUGGAAACACACUGAUAGAUGGAAAGUUAGUCCAUCUAUCUAAGACAUCCACAUCUAAGACAUAUGUGGAUAGAAGAGAUUAGGGGCAAGAGUGAAAGAAACAUACAGCCCCAGAGCAAUAGAUAAUACAUAUGGUGUUAGAGUUAGAGGAAAACAUAACAACCACAGGAGAGGGAGAUUUCAGCUAAUGAUUCCACACAUAGCAAGCUGCUUCUGUUUAUGGGCAGGAAGCUAUAAAGCUGCAACACUAGCACAUCAGGCCUUUCAAAGGCCUAUUUUUAGAAUGCUCCUGAUAAUGCCUCAGGAGUUGCUAGAUCUGAAUUAAAAACUCCAGGUCUCUACCUCCCCUCCUUUUCUAAGUAAAGGGUUAUUGAUUUACUAAUGGCCUUUGUAUCCUGCUGCAAAUAAAUCCUAUAGAAGAAGAAAGAUGUUACCUAGAGCCUGAGUGGCUAACAGCUUGGAAAAACCAAGCUCACAGGUAGACAGAUAGAAGGCAAACUUUGAGAAAACUUUGAACCUGAGGCAAAGGGAGGAAUCAUGCAGGGUGGGAAGGAGGCAUUUAAGGGGGAAGAGUAGGGUUGCUGAAAACAAGUGUUGUCAUAGGAUGCAGCCAUGUAAGGGCGGGCAUGUGGAAGUCCUGUGUGGAUAACAGAGUCCUGCAGGCAUUUGUUGGAACCAGAGAUUUGUCAGAGGAGUGGGGUGCAACCAAGGGUCUCUGGGCUGAGUGGCAAAUACAUGCCUCGAAUCUGGUCCCAGCUGUACCAUUAGUCGCAUAUGUAAGUCUAAACCUCAGAAUCUGGAUUCUGCAUCUUUCUCUAUGAAACAAAGGGCCUUUGUGAUGAGUCUAGAAUUCCAGAUGUCAGUUGCCGACAUGGUGGCCGUUUUCCUGGAAUAUUUCUCUGGCUACAUUGGUUACAGUUUCUCUCUGGUUGCUUCCCUUUCCCUGCUCCCUCAAAAAAGGCUGGUUCCUGGGGCUGAGAGUUAGAAUAGGCCCUGGAGGUGGAAGGAGGUGAAGUGAGGAAAGUGAACCAAGAAGCUAAAUCUAGACAGGAGGCAGGAAAAGCAAAAUAAAGACAGAAAGACAGAAACCAGGAAAGAGAAAAGUCAGGCCAGAGUGGCCAGCAGUGCCAAACGCCGCAGACAAGUUAGGGUAAUGGGGGAGAAGUGGAUUGAGGGGUGUAGAACCUGGUGGUUACAACCUGCACUCUGGACCCAGACAACCCACUCUGGCCAUGAAAUGCUGCUUUAGAAAUUAAUCUCUUUAGCUCCUAAUUUCCUCAUCCAUAAAAAGAAUCUAACAGUAGAACACAAAGCUUUUUAUUGUCCUGUGGAUCAAAUGAGACAAUGUAUGAAAAGCAGUAAGAGCAAUGUCUGACACCCAGUCAUCGCUCAGUAAGUACUAGCCACAGGUACUAAGAUGCCUCCCAGGCUUGGAGACUGGAAAGUUGCCGCAGGUUUUGCAGAAGUCAAGCUUAAAGAUGUUUGUGGAAAGACAGGCAGGCACUGUAUGUAAGUAGGUUAAAGAACAGUGUUGAGAGGCAAAUUUGGGAAGGAUAGUUUUGUGUUUGAAACAAAUAUCCAACAAAUGAGAAUAAGUAGAUAAGUACUGUCUUUUAAAAAAGUGUACUUAACCAUUUCCCCACUCUCCUUAUCCCCUGGUGUGGUGACGGCUGUAACCCACUAACUGCUGGUAACUGCCCUUCAGAGAAAUGCAUCCCAGGUGCUGAAUCUGUAGAGAGUGUGCAUUAUUCUCUGGCCCCUUCUCCACUACAUUCUACAUUUGCAUCAUAGCCACAGAUUUUUUUUUUCUUCAUCUUCUUCUUUUUUCAGCUGUUGUCCUUUAACUGUUAUUUCCUUAAUGAACAGACUAAACCCCAGCUCCGCCUCACGCAAGUGGAGCAACCAAGUGUGAGACACUGAGAUCCUGGAAAUGAAAGGAUUGUCUGACCAGCUGUUCAAAUUGGUGGCUGAAGCUCUCCGCUCCGAGCCCUGGAGGAGCAGCACGGAGCGGGAGAGCGUGGCGAGAGAAUGAAGAAACCAAUCGCCCGGGAGAAGCAUGAGGUGGCAGUGUGGCACUCGGUUUAGAGGGCUUCGGCCGGCGGUGGCCCCAUGGACAGCCCUGCUGGCACUGGGCCUGCCUGGCUGGGUGUUGGCUGUCUCAGCCACGGCGGCUGCUGUGGUCCCCGAGCAGCAUGCCUCCGUAGCUGGCCAGCAUCCCCUGGACUGGCUGCUCACAGACCGGGGCCCCUUCCACCGCGCUCAGGAGUAUGCUGACUUCAUGGAGCGGUACCGCCAGGGUUUCACCACCAGGUACAGGAUUUAUAGGGAGUUUGCCCGUUGGAAGGUGAACAACUUGGCUCUGGAAAGGAAGGACUUCUUCAGUUUGCCAUUGCCUCUUGCCCCAGAGUUUAUCCGGAACAUUCGCCUCCUUGGAAGGAGACCCAAUCUGCAACAGGUUACAGAAAAUCUGAUUAAAAAGUACGGCACUCAUUUCUUACUUUCUGCCACCCUUGGAGGAGAAGAGUCCCUGACCAUUUUUGUGGACAAGCAGAAACUGGGAAGAAAGACAGAGACAACAGGAGGUGCCUCUAUAAUCGGGGGCAGUGGGAACAGCACAGCUGUGUCCCUGGAGACCCUGCACCAGCUGGCCGCCUCCUACUUCAUCGACAGAGAGAGCACGCUGCGACGGCUGCACCAUAUCCAGAUAGCCACGGGGGCCAUCAAGGUCACCGAGACCAGGACCGGUCCUCUGGGCUGCAGCAACUAUGACAAUCUGGACUCAGUCAGUUCUGUCUUGGUACAGAGUCCAGAGAACAAAGUACAGUUACUUGGCCUUCAGGUGCUGCUGCCUGAGUAUCUGCGUGAGCGCUUUGUAGCUGCAGCACUCAGCUACAUCACAUGCAGCUCUGAGGGUGAGCUCGUCUGCAAGGAGAAUGACUGCUGGUGCAAGUGCAGCCCCACCUUCCCUGAAUGCAACUGCCCUGAUGCUGACAUCCAGGCCAUGGAGGACAGCCUGCUGCAGAUCCAGGACUCCUGGGCCACUCACAACCGGCAGUUUGAAGAGUCAGAAGAGUUCCAGGCCCUGCUGAAAAGGCUGCCCGAUGACCGGUUCCUGAACUCCACAGCUAUCUCCCAGUUCUGGGCCAUGGACACCAGCCUUCAGCACCGCUACCAGCAGCUGGGAGCUGGCUUGAAAGUGCUGUUCAAAAAGACCCAUCGGAUCCUACGCCGGCUCUUCAACCUCUGCAAGCGCUGCCAUCGCCAGCCUCGCUUCCGCCUGCCCAAGGAGAGGUCCUUGUCCUACUGGUGGAACCGAAUCCAGUCCCUCCUCUACUGUGGGGAAAGCACCUUUCCUGGCACUUUCCUGGAACAGAGCCACAGCUGCACCUGCCCCUAUGACCAAUCUUCCUGCCAGGGCCCCAUCCCAUGUGCCUUGGGCGAAGGGCCCGCGUGUGCCCACUGUGCUCCAGACAAUAGCACACGCUGUGGGAGCUGCAACCCGGGCUAUGUGCUGGCCCAGGGGCUGUGCCGGCCAGAGGUGGCCGAGUCCCUGGAAAACUUUCUUGGGCUGGAGACAGACUUGCAGGACCUGGAGCUAAAGUACCUGCUGCAGAAGCAGGAUAGCCGCAUUGAGGUACACUCCAUCUUCAUCAGCAAUGACAUGCGGCUGGGCAGCUGGUUUGACCCUUCCUGGAGGAAGCGCAUGCUGCUCACCCUGAAGAGCAACAAGUACAAGCCUGGGCUGGUGCACGUGAUGUUGGCCUUGUCCUUGCAGAUCUGUCUCACCAAGAACAGCACCCUGGAGCCUGUCAUGGCCAUCUACGUCAACCCCUUUGGGGGCAGCCACUCUGAGAGCUGGUUCAUGCCUGUGAAUGAGGGCAGCUUUCCUGACUGGGAAAGGACUAACGUGGAUGCAGCUGCCCAGUGCCAAAACUGGACUAUCACCUUGGGGAAUAGGUGGAAGACUUUCUUUGAGACAGUUCAUGUUUACCUACGGAGCCGAAUCAAGUCCCUGGAUGACAGCUCCAAUGAGACAAUCUACUAUGAGCCCCUGGAGAUGACUGAUCCCUCUAAGAAUUUGGGUUACAUGAAAAUUAACACCUUGCAGGUCUUUGGCUACAGCCUGCCCUUUGACCCAGAUGCUAUCCGGGACUUAAUUCUCCAGUUGGACUACCCAUAUACUCAAGGUUCCCAGGACUCUGCACUCUUGCAGCUCAUUGAGCUCAGGGACCGGGUGAACCAGCUUUCUCCACCUGGCAAAGUCCGACUUGACCUUUUCUCCUGCUUGCUCCGGCAUCGGCUUAAGCUGGCCAACAAUGAGGUGGGCAGGAUCCAGUCCUCCCUGAGGGCUUUCAAUUCUAAGCUGCCAAACCCUGUGGAAUAUGAGACCGGCAAACUCUGUAGCUAAUGGGCGGCCCACUUCAGCACUGGGCAAGGAGGGGAUCCAUGAAUCUGGGGUACAAAGAUAAUCUAAGCCCUCACCUUAGUGCCAACAGGGUGUGCUCCCACGAGACUUUCAGCAUCCAGUAGAUGGGACCUCGAGGCUCGAGCUGAAGCAGGCGAGAGAGAAACAGCUACUGCGUGCGUGCGCGCACGCAUACACACACACACACACACACUGGCACAGGGAGGCUACAACUAAGCAGCCUCAGAUCUGUAAAGUUGAUUGGUGCUUUCUAAAAUGAAUGCAAUUGAAAGAAAGGAGCCAAGGAAGAGAUUAAGAAAAAGAACCAGCUGAACCAUGAAACAAACAAAAAUCCUAAAAGUGAUUCUUGUCAUUCAAGAAAGCAAGAGGGGACAACAAUGGGAGGGGUCGGAGCUCUUCCUUCCCCUCUGUGGAGUCACUUUUGUAUUCUUUUUAACCAGAUUUCUUAAAAUGUUGUUGUUUUGUGAAUCCUGACAUUGGUUCUUACUUUUGUAUGCUGCCUCCUCUGUGCCCUCCCAGACGCUGACUGGGAAACACAAGAAGUACAACCAACAGGAACCAGCGCCAAGGGCAGGCAGCGGCCUCCUUGCUCCCCUCCCUUACUCCUCCCUCUGCUGCCUCCUCCCCCCACCAAGUUUCAGGGCCCUGGAUUGUUCCCAGUUCCCAUUGUGGUCCCUUCAGAGCUCCUUUCCAACAGCAUCUCUCUGUCGAAGAAAGAAGCUCUGUCAAGUUAGAGAGAGACAAUGUGUAGGAAAUGUUCUUUUUUAAAAAAAAAUAACAAAAACAAAACAAAACUAUUUAUUUUGUGAUUGUUUUCCUUGUUAAUCUGCUCCAACCACCUGAACAUCUAAGUAAACAUUUAUCUGGUUUAAUAUA